GAGAGAGACUUCCUUGGGGAGAGGAAUUCAGCUGCACGCUGGAGUCAGCUGGAGUUGCCCAGGCCCUGUGAGCAAGUGGCAGGCGUGCCCAGCUGCAUUGGGGAGAGGGCUGUUCUCAAGGCCAAGGUCAUUUUUGGAGGGAGAACUGGACGCCUGAUCAAAUCUGGCCCACAAUGGACUCAGCAGCCAAGGAUGAGAUGCAGCCGGCGUUGUCCCCUGGACCUGAGUGGCCAGAGCAGGAGCGGGCAGAGCAGCUGGCCCGGGGUGCAGCGCUCAAGUGGGCCUCAGGCAUCUUCUACCGGCCGGAGCAGCUGGCCAGGCUAGGCCAGUACCGCAGCCGCGAGGUGCAGCGUACCUGCUCCCUGGAAUCGCGCCUCAAGUCAGUGAUGCAGUCAUACCUGGAAGGCGUGCAGACUGGUGUGUGGCAGCUGGCCCAGGCCAUUGAGGUGGUGCAGGGAACCCGGGAGGCCCUGAGCCAGGCCCGUGGGUUGCUCCAGGGCAUGUCCCAGGCCUUACAGACUCUAGAGCCCCUACGGGAGCGGGUUGCCCAGCACAAGCAACUGCAGGCCCUGUCUCACCUGCUGCCUCGGCUGCGGGCAGUGCCGGCUGCAGUGUCCCACACACAGACUCUGAUUGAUGGCCAACAGUUCUUGGAGGCAUAUGUGAGCCUUCGGGAGCUGGAGCAGCUGCGAGAGGAUACGUGGGCACCCCUGGGGGGCCUGGAGUUGCCAGUCUUCCAGGGGCUGGACCUUCUGUUCGAGGCACUGGGCCAGGCUGUGGAAGCAGCUGCAGGGGCCGCAGGGAAGCUGGCACGGGAGGACCCAGCCCUGUUGGUGGCUGCUGUGCGUGUGGCGGAGGUGGAGACUGGACGAACAACCCCCCUGGGCCAGGUCCCCCGGGACUGGCGUCAGCGCUGUCUGAGGGCACUACAGGAGGGCCUGGAGCAGGCCCACUUUGGGUCACCUCUGCUGCCUGCACCAGGGGCCCUACCAGGGUGGCUGGAGGCUCUGCGAGUGGCCCUGCCAGUCGAGUUGGCCACAGCUGAGGCACUAGUAGCGCCUUGCUGCCCGCCACAGUACAACGUGGUCCAGCUAUGGGCCCACACGCUGCAUAGUGGUUUGCGCCGCAGCCUGCAGAACCUCCUUGCAGGGCCUGAGCUAGAAGCUGCGGAUGCCUUCGCCUUGCUGCACUGGGCACUGCAUGUGUACCUGGGGCAGGAAAUGAUGGGGAGCCUGGAGUUGGGGCCUGAGGCUGAUGUGUCCCAGCUGGAGCCCCUUCUGACCUUGGAGAACAUUGAGCAGCUGGAGGCAACAUUUGUGGCCAACAUCCAGGCAAGUGUGUCUCAGUGGCUGCAGAAUGCACUGGAUGGGGAGGUAGCUGAGUGGGGCCGGGAGCAUGGGCCCAACACAGACCCGUCUGGCUCCUAUUACUCACCAAUGCCAGCCAUUGUGCUGCAGAUCCUGGAAGAGAACAUUCGUGUGGCCAGCCUGGUCAGUGAGUCACUGCAACAGCGAGUGCAUGGCAUGGCACUGUCAGAACUGGGCACAUUCUUGAGGAGCUUCAGUGAUGCUCUGAUCCGAUUCUCCCGAGACCACUUCAGGGGGAAAUCAAUGGCCCCUCAUUACGUGCCCUACCUACUGGCCGCCCUCAACCACAAGUCAGCACUCAGCUCCUCAGUGUCUGUCCUGCAGCUGGACGGGGCGCCUUCAGGGGCCUUGGCUCCAGUGGAAGCUGCGCUGGACGAGUUGCAGAGGAGGAUCUACCGCUUGGUGUUGGAGGCGCUGCAGGCGGAGCUCCAGCCCCUGUUCGCGGAUCUGCCCUCGCGCCAAUGGCUGUCGAGCCCUGAGCUCCUGCAAAGUGUGUGUGAACGGACGGGGCGCUUCUGCCGGGACUUCUGGCGCGUGCGGAACCCCACGGUUCAGCUGCUGCUGGCUGAGGCCGAGCGUGCCGUGGUGCUCCAGUACCUGAGCGCGCUGAUGCAAGGCCGCCUGGUGUGCCGCGGAGCCGACGAGAGGACCCAGGCGGCCGAGCGCCUGCGGCACGAUGCUGCCCAGCUUCAGCAGCUUUUCCUCAGUUUGGGCCUGGAGGAGAACGCGCACUGCGCGCCGGUGCUGCUCGCCCUGAGGGAGCUGCUAAACCUCCGCGACCCCGCGCUGCUGGGCCUGGAGGUGGCUGGCCUGCGGCAACAAUUUCCCGACGUGAGCGAGGACCACGUCUCCGCCCUCUUGGGCCUGCGCGGGGACUUGUCCCGGGAGCAGCACCUGGCCGCGCUCAGCUCCCUGCAGGCUGCGCUGCCGCCGUCGCCCCGCGCGAGCCGCCGCGUCCUCUUCAGCCUAGUGCCCGCGCCCGCGCUCGCGCCGGCCUCCUGCCUGCCCUCGGGGUCCUGCGCCCGAGCCCUGCUGCUCGCAGAAUAAACCACGGCUGCCGGA